AACUAGGGACGGAGCAAGCGGGCGAGCUAGAGAGCGUCCCCGAGCCAUGGUCUCUACCGGCCGCGGCUCAGCCUGGGUCCCUCUGCUCUCAACCCGAGUGCCCGAUGGAGGCUUUGGUUUCAUGUCAGCAGCCUUCAUCUGCCUUCCAAAAAUAAGCCCCUGCCGCCAUGCCGGAGGGAGAAAAACAAGAAGGGCGGUAUUUUUAGGGCCAUUAAUUCUGACCACGUGCCUGAGAGGCAAGGUGGAUGGCCCUGGGACAGAAACUGUUCAUCACUAUGUCCCGGGGAGCAGGACGUCUGCAGGGCACGCUGUGGGCUCUCGUCUUCCUAGGCAUCCUAGUGGGCAUGGUGGUGCCCUCGCCUGCAGGCACCCGUGCCAACAACACGCUGCUGGACUCGAGGGGCUGGGGCACCCUGCUGUCCAGGUCUCGCGCCGGGCUAGCUGGAGAGAUUGCCGGGGUGAACUGGGAAAGUGGCUAUUUGGUGGGGAUCAAGCGGCAGCGGAGGCUCUACUGCAACGUGGGCAUCGGCUUUCACCUCCAGGUGCUCCCCGACGGCCGGAUCAGCGGGACCCACGAGGAGAACCCCUACAGCCUGCUGGAAAUUUCCACUGUGGAGCGAGGCGUGGUGAGUCUCUUUGGAGUGAGAAGUGCCCUCUUCGUUGCCAUGAACAGUAAAGGAAGAUUGUACGCAACGCUGCGGACACCCGGUCUCCAGGGUCACACGUCCAGCCACAGCUGUGUGCAGCCCCGUCUCAGGGCUCCGCGACCCGAGUUCCAGUUCCUGGCCAACCUACCCUCCAGCUACUCGUCUUACUUUGGGCAACGUCACUGAACUUCUCUGGGCCUGGAUCUCUGCUCUCUGAGGAUGAGGCAGAAAUCAGUGAAUUCUAGCCCCCUUGGUCCCCUUUGAAAUUCAGAAAACAAAAUAUCAAGGAUCUCCACCUGACAGUGGUUCUAUUAGAAUCCUUUGGUUGAGAAAAAUAUAUACUAGUAAAAAGAUACCAGCAAUUCGGUCGUGCUUUCAAGUGAUUUCAGUUUUACUAAGAAGAGCCGCAUUUACAUGCUUUUCGUCAACAGUAUGACAAUGUGCAAAGGACAAAAUUGAUUUCCUCCAGAGACCUUUGAUUAUUAUCUGGGGCAUUACAUUGGGGCAUUAUUAUCUGGGGCAUUGCAUUAUUAUCUGGGGCAUUACAUUAUUAUCUGGGGCAUUACAAGGCUGGGAGGACCAGCCUUGCCUUGGCUCAGCUGCCACUGUAGCAGAAAACAGCACUCCUGAGGGAAUGGGAUGAAGGACACCCACCAUGAGGAAGUGCUGGGAGAUGGGGCUGGAGAGCAGCGGGAGGUGCAUGCCCUUAUGCAGGGCCUGAGGCUCUGCAUACAAAUCCCCGCCUGCUACAAAGAGCUGCACUGGAGUGAGAAGAAUGAAACACCUGAUGAAAACACUUUCCAACAUUCCUAAAUCAACAGUUCAAUUGUGUGCUAGGAAAAAGGGUUGGAAAAUGCAGGCAUCUUCAGAGCUGAUGAUAUUUCAGCUAAAGACAGGAAAAGAAGCAGUCAGGGGCUACAGAAGAAAGUCUUAGGACAAAGAAUUGGUUUAUUUUUCCUUCUUGCCCACAUCCUUCCACCCCAUCCUUCUCCAUCCAACACACACUGCCAGGAGGAACAGGGACAAAUGGCCCCAGCGGUCACAGGGUGAAGAUGUUUAAAAGCAGGAUUAGAUCCUCGUUGGUCCAAGUGACUUAGCUCUAAAGGCGAGAGGGUGGCUGUCUUGUCCACCUCACACUUUGGAGGCACCUCUACCCCAUGGAUAUGCUUGCUCCUCUGAGAAAUGCCCUUCUCCAUAGUGAGUGCCAAAUGCACAUAAGUCUGAAUAGACCUACAUCAAAUUGAAGAUAUUUUCAUGCUGGGGCUUGAGCCUGGCAGGCCCAGGAAAUGUGACCCAGUGGAAUGAUUUUCAUUUAUUCAAGUAAUCAUAUACAGUAGCUGCUUUUAUGAACAUGGCGUUCACUUGGCUCGAGUGCGUUCUUCACCAGAGCUGAGGGGCCAACAUUCCCAAGCCAUGAGAACUCAAAGCUCAGGGCUCUGAUGAAGAUGAAUUAAGGGGCUGGGUCUUGAGCAUCACUCUGGGCAUCGGGAAAAUCCCAUCAGCCUGAAGCAUUCAGAAAAAAUGCACUAUCUCUCCUUCAUGCCACAGGCCUCCUGGCCUUCCAAACCCCACAGAUGUGGGUGCUGAGGGCGGAGGAGAGAGAGCAGCAAGGGGAAGGUUAGGGCUUCUAACACAAGCUUCCUCUACUAGUUGUCUUUUUUCACUUUAGUUUUGUACAGGAUUCUGGGGAAGGCCAGGGAUAUGAGACAGGCUAGAGAAAAGGGCAGAAUGGAAAGAAAAAAAAGUAGUAAACUUGAAAAAAAAAUAGAAACAGAAAAAAAAAAAGUGUGUAUGUUGAGGGGGAGUGGAUUUGAAUGAUCCAAAAUCGAAUGACCAGAGAAGCAAAGUACAAUCUACGCAUCCAUGGUCAUGCAUGCUUAAACAAUCAUGUUUUAGGAGAUCCAGAUGUUUAGGAGAGGCUGGGUUCUCAAAUGGGCACAUUCUAGGCACGGGGAAGUGGGCAAUGGCUUGAGAGUUUCUUGUCCAAGUCACUCAGUUCCUCCCACUUCCCCUUCCUCCACCUCAAGAUUUCAUUUCCUCACUAGAGCUUGCAAACAACACACGAAACCUCUCCCUUAACCACCAUCCAGAUCAGAAAUAAAUUCUCUGGAACUGACUGGGCGGGUUACUCUCCAGGGACAUACAAAGUUAGAACAGGGGGGAGGCUGGUGGGUGGAGAGGGGCCGUGACCCAACAAGAAGGAGACCACCAGUUUCUGAUCAAAAUGUUUUCUCGCUUCGUUUCCUGGCCCAUUUGCUACCCUAAAUUCCCUUCCCACUUUAAAUAAUUUACGUACUUGACUAGGUAACACAGGAACAUGUUUUAAGGAGAAAAAAGUAUCAAAGAAUAUUCUAUGGAAAGUCUCACUCCCACCAUUGUCUUGAAGCCACUGAGUUCCUCCCUAGAGGCAGCCCCAGUUACCAGUGUUUCAUUCCAGUAUAUCGUUCCAGAAAUAGCUAACGCACACGUGCACGCACCGGUAUCAUCUUUUUUAAAAAAUCACACAAACAAGAGCGUACUAUGCCAACACUUUUUCAAACCUUGUGUCUUCACUUAGCAAUGUAUCUU